AGGAGCCACCGAGAGCCAGACCUCCGCGAUCCCUAGAGGGGCCGAACACCUCUGGGCAAUGGGCCCGGCCGGCUCCCCGGCCGCACUUCCGGGCGCGGAGGUUACAGCCCAUCGCCGAGCCUUACCCGCUCGCAGUCCCGGUUCCCGAGCUCCUGCCGCCGUCGCCCUGUGGAGGACACCCCUGCCGGCCCCGCAGUCCCUCCUCGACUUGCGCUGGCUUCGGCCGUCCUGGAACUCGAGCUCGUUCCCCCCUCCGAGCCUUUUGCCCUUGCGGUUCCCGCUGCUGGGAACGACCUUGCCCUCAGCCGCCUGGCUGGUCCCUGCGCCGCUGCAGUGCGAAUGUCGCCUUCUCAGGGGCCCUUUCUCUUCCUUCGUUGCAACACUGAAGUCCUCUUGUUUGAUGACUUGCGUGAGGUUAUUCCUCCCACUUAGGAGGCUGAGUGCUGCGAGGUCCGAGGCGCAGCCGCUCUUCGCUGUGUCCGGCCCGGCGUGCUCCCGACAGGGGGCGUCACUGAACAGCGACCGUCUCCGUCGCCCACUCGGCCCUGGUGUUUGCUUUUUGGUGUGUUUACACCGCGCACCUGGGGGAGAGGGGCGGGCCUUCACGAGGGCGCGGGCCACACCCGUGUGGAGGCUUCGGGCACAGCCCAGGACCUGA